AGACACAGGCUGAGGAUCGGCACGGGAGCAUGGCAGCCAACGUCUCGGGUGCCAAGUCCUGCCCUGCCAACUUCUUGGCAGCUGCCGACGACAAACUCAGUGGGUUCCAGGGGGACUUCCUGUGGCCCAUACUGGUGGUUGAGUUCCUGGUGGCCGUGGCCAGCAAUGGCCUGGCCCUGUACCGCUUCAGCAUCCGGAAGCAGCGCCCAUGGCACCCCGCCGUGGUCUUCUCUGUCCAGCUGGCAGUCAGCGACCUGCUCUGCGCCCUGACGCUGCCCCCGCUGGCCGCCUACCUCUAUCCCCCCAAGCACUGGCGCUAUGGGGAGGCCGCGUGCCGCCUGGAGCGCUUCCUCUUCACCUGCAACCUGCUGGGCAGCGUCAUCUUCAUCACCUGCAUCAGCCUCAACCGCUACCUGGGCAUCGUGCACCCCUUCUUCGCCCGAAGCCACCUGCGACCCAAGCACGCCUGGGCCGUGAGCGCUGCCGGCUGGGUCCUGGCCGCCCUGCUGGCCAUGCCCACACUCAGCUUCUCCCACCUGAAGAGGCCGCAGCAGGGGGCGGGCAACUGCAGCGUGGCCAGGCCCGAGGCCUGCAUCAAGUGUCUGGGGACAGCAGACCACGGGCUGGCGGCCUACAGAGCGUAUAGCCUGGUGCUGGCGGGGUUGGGCUGCGGCCUGCCGCUGCUGCUCACGCUGGCAGCCUACGGCGCCCUCGGGCGGGCCGUGCUACGCAGCCCAGGCAUGACUGUGGCCGAGAAGCUGCGUGUGGCAGCGUUGGUGGCCAGUGGUGUGGCCCUCUACGCCAGCUCCUAUGUGCCCUACCACAUCAUGCGGGUGCUCAACGUGGAUGCUCGGCGGCGCUGGAGCACCCGCUGCCCGAGCUUUGCAGACAUAGCCCAGGCCACAGCAGCCCUGGAGCUGGGGCCCUACGUGGGCUACCAGGUGAUGCGGGGCCUCAUGCCCCUGGCCUUCUGUGUCCACCCUCUACUCUACAUGGCCGCAGUGCCCAGCCUGGGCUGCUGCUGCCGACACUGCCCCGGCUACAGGGACAGCUGGAACCCAGAGGACGCCAAGAGCACUGGCCAAGCCCUGCCCCUCAAUGCCACAGCCGCCCCUAAACCGUCAGAGCCCCAGUCCCGUGAGCUGAGCCAAUGAUGUGGCCUAGCGGAAGCUGCCUCCUCACCCUAGGUGUUGCUGGAGAACCCUGAGGGCAGGGCCCGAGCCCCGACACAUCCCUUCCCCCAAAAAGCAACACCUGUGCUUGCAGCCAGGUCAGGCCCAGCUGCAGCCCAGGCAGGAGCAGUCGCCUUUCCCACCCACAGCGCUGGCCACAGGGCUCCCUGCAGGGUCAGGGACCAGACCACGCCCAGAGGAGGGGAGGCACUGGCCCCCGCCACAGGACUGGAGACGCAAGAACAAAAAGAACCAAGUAGAGAGAGUGGAGCUGCUUUAUUGCCCUUGGAGCCCGCGCUCUCGGAGGCUGUCUUCUGUCGCCAAGGGUCCCGGACCGAGUACACAGUGGCAGCUGGCUUAGUUGGUGGACGGCCUGGGGUAGGGGAGGGUGGCAGGUAUAAGACUUCUGGGGGCACCCCAAGACCCCAGACACCCAAGUGGCAUCUUGGGGGUGGGUGGGCAGAGGACGGGGUAAUGUGAGGACGAAGCGGGCACGGAGCCAGAUGGCCAGUCUCCAGGCCUGGUCCACGGACUGGCAGGGACCCCAGGCACAAGAGCUGCCACCCCUCUGCCCGGUUUUGGAAAAAAACAAUAAAGGACUGUCCCCUCAAAACCA